GUUGGCGGCGUGGAGGGGCGCCGGUGGCCACGUUGGUGUCAACCUCCUUCGUGAAGCUCACACCUCCCCCGCCCCGGGAGGGGUUUGCCCGCCACUGUCGCUGAAUGAUUGCAUCAUCGAAAGCAGAAAACCACUUUUGCAUCCUUCGGCCUCUGGCGUGCCUGCCAUGACGUCAUAGCUCUGCGGAGGUGGAAGUUGGGGAGCUUUGAGGUAACUGGAUUCUUGAUCUGAGCGCAGACGUCCUUCCUAACCUCACUGCAUUUGGAGGACCUGGAGGGAGGGUGGGUGAAGGGCAAGGAAAGAGGCAGGAUGAGAGCUUGGCCGCGGUGGCGUCUGAGGGGCCUGAAUGUUUCAAGGCCAGAGCCUGGCGAUCAGGUGGCUCGCUUAGUCCUAAACCAGUCAUCCUUCUCCAGGCCUCCUCUGUAGAAUGGAAACUCUGUACCCCUGCUUGUCUUAGGACCUCAUGGAUCCCAGGGGGACCAAGAGAGGAGCUGAGAAGACAGAGGUAGCUGAGCCUCGGAACAAACUACCUCGUCCAGCACCUUCUCUGCCCACAGACCCUGCCCUCUACUCUGGGCCCUUUCCUUUCUACCGGCGCCCUUCGGAACUGGGCUGCUUCUCCCUGGAUGCUCAACGCCAGUACCAUGGAGAUGCCCGAGCCCUGCGCUACUAUAGCCCACCCCCCACUAACGGUCCAGGCCCCAACUUUGACCUCAGAGACGGAUACCCGGAUCGAUACCAGCCCCGGGACGAGGAGGUCCAGGAAAGGCUGGACCACCUGCUGUGCUGGCUCCUGGAACACCGAGGCCGGUUGGAGGGGGGUCCAGGCUGGCUGGCAGAGGCCAUAGUGACGUGGCGGGGGCACCUGACAAAACUGCUGACGACACCGUAUGAGCGGCAGGAGGGCUGGCAGCUGGCAGCCUCCCGGUUCCAGGGAACACUAUACCUGAGUGAAGUGGAGACACCGAACGCUCGGGCCCAGAGGCUUGCUCGGCCACCGCUCCUCCGGGAGCUUAUGUACAUGGGAUACAAAUUUGAGCAGUACAUGUGUGCAGACAAACCUGGAAGCUCCCCAGACCCCUCUGGGGAGGUUAACACCAACGUGGCCUUCUGCUCUGUGCUACGCAGCCGCCUGGGAAGCCACCCUCUGCUCUUCUCAGGGGAGGUAGACUGCACAGACCCCCAAGCCCCAUCCACACAGCCCCCAACCUGCUAUGUGGAGCUCAAGACCUCCAAGGAGAUGCACAGCCCUGGCCAAUGGAGGAGUUUCUACAGACACAAGCUCCUGAAAUGGUGGGCUCAGUCAUUCCUCCCAGGGGUCCCGAAUGUUGUUGCUGGCUUCCGUAACCCAGACGGUUUUGUCUCUUCCCUCAAGACCUUUCCUACCAUGAAGAUGUUUGAAUAUGUCAGGAAUGACCGUGACGGCUGGAAUCCCUCUGUGUGCAUGAACUUCUGUGCCGCCUUCCUUAGCUUUGCCCAGAGCACGGUUGUCCAGGAUGACCCCAGGCUCGUUCAUCUCUUCUCUUGGGAGCCUGGCGGCCCAGUCACCGUGUCUGUACACCAAGAUGCACCUUACGCCUUCCUGCCCAUAUGGUAUGUGGAAGCUAUGACUCAGGACCUCCCAUCACCCCCCAAGACUCCCUCUCCCAAAUAGUAAUGCUUUAGAGGGAGGCAGUCAUAUCUCUGUGUGCAGAUAAUAAAAGCAUAUUUCUAAGA